AUACUGCCUCCAUGCAAGCCCAGAAUAACCUGGAUGUGUGACUCACAGGGGUAGGGGUAGCAAUUUUGCAGAUUUUCCAAACAGGUGACUUCAGCCCCCGGGCCUGGGCAGGAAGGGGUAGCCCAGUGACAAUGGGCAUAGUCCCACUUCAGGAACGGGAAACGUGUUGGCUGGCUCUGUGGAGUUCUCUCUCUUCUGAUCCCACAGCAUCUGUUCCAGUUGUCUUGGCCGCUGGGGUAUGGCCGUCAAUGUGUACUCCACAUCUGUGACCAGUGAAAAUCUGAGUCGCCAUGAUAUGCUUGCAUGGGUCAACGACUCCCUGCACCUCAACUAUACCAAGAUAGAACAGCUUUGUUCAGGGGCAGCCUACUGCCAGUUCAUGGACAUGCUCUUCCCCGGCUGUGUGCACUUGAGGAAAGUGAAGUUCCAGGCCAAACUAGAGCACGAAUACAUCCACAACUUCAAGGUGCUGCAAGCAGCUUUCAAGAAGAUGGGUGUUGACAAAAUCAUUCCUGUAGAGAAAUUAGUGAAAGGAAAAUUCCAAGAUAAUUUUGAGUUUAUUCAGUGGUUUAAGAAAUUCUUUGACGCAAACUAUGAUGGAAAGGAUUACAACCCUCUGCUGGCGCGGCAGGGCCAGGACGUAGCGCCACCUCCUAACCCAGGUGAUCAGAUCUUCAACAAAUCCAAGAAACUCAUUGGCACAGCAGUUCCACAGAGGACGUCCCCCACAGGCCCAAAAAACAUGCAGACCUCUGGCCGGCUGAGCAAUGUGGCCCCCCCCUGCAUUCUCCGGAAGAAUCCUCCAUCAGCCCGAAAUGGCGGCCAUGAGACUGAUGCCCAAAUUCUUGAACUCAACCAACAGCUGGUGGACUUGAAGCUGACAGUGGAUGGGCUGGAGAAGGAACGUGACUUCUACUUCAGCAAACUUCGUGACAUCGAGCUCAUCUGCCAGGAGCAUGAAAGUGAAAACAGCCCUGUUAUCUCAGGCAUCAUUGGCAUCCUCUAUGCCACAGAGGAAGGAUUCGCACCCCCUGAGGACGAUGAGAUUGAAGAGCAUCAACAAGAAGACCAGGACGAGUACUGAGGGCGGCCGCAGCCCUGGCUGACUGCACAGCUUCCCCGUGCCUCCCUCCCUGCUCCACUCCCACAUUAUAGUCCUUUCCUAACACGGUCGGCCGGGUGCUUUGUGUCAGUGCUGCAGCACUGGGGAGCCAGGCGAGGGGGGCUUGGGGGCAUGGGGCCGGAAAGCAGGCAGAAGCCCGUCCUGGGUGGUGCUGGCCCAGUUGGUGGGACCCCUGUCCACACCCACCCUAUUUAUUUCCGUUGUCUCUCUGCUGUGUCGCCCAACACUUCCCAGGGUGCUGCUGCCACCCGCCCCAGCCAGCCACCUGCUCCUGACAGCCAGCAGCUGUGUAUUUGACAAAGUCAUUGGUAUAUUUUUACUUACUGGAUUCUCCUUGCACUUUACCUGUUCUUUUCCAGAGCUGACAGCACGGGCUCCGGCGCAGUGUGCCUGGCUUGGCUUCCCUUCCCCAUGGCUGGGGGCUGGGGUAGGACUCACCCAUUCUAAUUUAUUUUGUCUUUUGGCUUCUCAGUAGCUAAGGGGAAGGCUGAUGUCAGGAGAGGGAGAGGGGGCUGAGGAGGUAGUGCUGUAGGCCCAGGGGGUCAGGGAAAGGGAGGGGGGCAUGUGAGGGAUGGAAAUGACCUCCUGGCACCAGGCUCACCCACCCAAGGCCCCCUGCCCCAGCACUGAAUCCCAGCGCUGCCCUGAGGCCCCCAGCCACUCCCUCCAGCAGCCUGGUUCACCACACAAACUCUGCCUGGACCCCAUUGUCUGUCUGCUUCCCACCUGCCCUCCCCACCCCCUGCCCCUCGGGCACCAGCCUGCAUAUGUGUUCACUUUUAUUUAAAUAAACUUGUGUGGUAAAAGUACAUGCCAUGUGUCCCUCAACUGA